GCCAUUUGUCUAUGGCAGGCAGGGUGGCUGCCUUAGCUGCCGGAGGUUCCGCACUCUCUAAGGCCCCGGGUGAAGCCCCACCUCUGCUGCGCGCAGCCUGCGGUGCGGGUCAUGGCGCGGCUACCGAAGCUGGCAGUCUUUGAUUUGGAUUACACUCUCUGGCCUUUCUGGGUCGACACGCACGUAGACCCUCCGUUCCAUAAGAGCAGUGAUGGAACUGUACGAGAUAGGCGGGGCCAAGACGUCCGACUGUACCCAGAGGUGCCUGAGGUCCUAAAACGAUUGCAGAGCCUUGGGGUGCCCGGUGCGGCUGCUUCAAGGACAAGUGAGAUAGAAGGGGCCAACCAGCUACUGGAGCUCUUUGACCUCUUCAGGUACUUUGUUCAUCGGGAAAUCUAUCCAGGCAGCAAGAUCACACACUUUGAGAGGUUGCAGCAGAAGACUGGAAUUCCUUUCUCCCAGAUGAUCUUCUUUGAUGAUGAGAGGCGGAAUAUUGUAGACGUCAGCAAACUGGGUACUGAGUGAUGAGGAACAGCCAUUUGGGGUCCCUAGGAGGGAUUAGGUGUUACCUGCAUUCACAUCCAGAAUGGAAUGAAUCUUCAAACUCUAAGUCAAGGGUUAGAGACAUUUGCGAAGGCCCAAACUGGGCCUUUGAGGUCCAGCCUUGAGGAGAGCCCAUUUGAGGCCUAAACUGAAAGGAAAUCAAGAAGGCAUUUUCAGGUGCAUUUGUAAUUUAUUAAAGUUCAUCUGUGUGUGACAGAAGAGAUUUUA